CUUUGCCCUUCCUGCGCCGCGUCCGCCACGCCGAAUUCCGGAAAGGCCCCAGUCCUGCGGAUGCGGCCGCGCGUUGCCGACGGUGGACGGAGGAAGCAGCCGGCGGGACAGGCUGGCCAGCUGGGGCGGCCCGGAGUCUGAGCCUAGAGCCUGGCGCCGCGAGUUACUUCCAGAAACAAGACUUUUCUCCCGGCCACCCCCCAAACGGGAUUUAAUGUAAUACACACGAGUUUCAUCAUGUGCGUCUUCCCCGUCUCUCUCCCAAGUUCAAAAGAGUCCCACGAACUGGCUGGGUAUACAGAAAUGUCCAGAGGCCGGAGAGCGUUUCAGAUCACAUGUACCGGAUGGCAGUUAUGGCUAUGGUGAUCAAAGAUGACCGUCUUAACAAAGACCGAUGUGUACGCCUAGCCCUGGUUCAUGAUAUGGCAGAAUGCAUCGUUGGGGACAUAGCACCAGCAGAUAACAUCCCCAAAGAAGAAAAACAUAGGCGAGAAGAGGAAGCUAUGAAGCAGAUAACCCAGCUCCUACCAGAGGACCUCAGAAAGGAGCUCUAUGAACUUUGGGAAGAGUACGAGACCCAAUCUAGUGCAGAAGCCAAAUUUGUGAAGCAGCUAGACCAAUGUGAAAUGAUUCUUCAAGCAUCUGAAUAUGAAGACCUUGAACACAAACCUGGGAGACUGCAAGACUUCUAUGAUUCCACAGCAGGAAAAUUCAAUCACCCUGAGAUAGUCCAGCUUGUUUCUGAACUUGAGGCAGAAAGAAGCACUAACAUAGCUGCAGCUGCCAGUGAGCCACACUCCUGAGACACUCUCUAAAUUGCUGCACUCCUGUAACAAACAUUAUUUUUCCAUUUCAUUGUAUUGUGUUUUGCCAUUGUUGGUCUGUUGAUUUCCCUAGAUGUGAGUCUGUUUGUUUUCAAUUGUCUGAACUUCAGCAAGAAAUGUGAUACAACUUGGGCACUAAAAGAAGCCACAGAACAGGAAGCGGUCAUGAAAGUGCCAUGGAUGAACACUGGAGGUGGCAGUGCCUGUUUAUGAACUAAAUAAAUAAAUAUUAAACACCUAAAAUAUUAGAAUAUUUAUUGGAGAUUUAAAAUCAUCUUAUUCUGACUUAAUUACCGAUAUCCCCGAAGGCUAGGUUCAUUGAAUAAUAGAAAAUUUCAUUAUGAUUGCUUUUAAGAACAGAUUCUUCAGCUGAUUUAGUGAUAAGAAUCCAGAAAAGAAAAUGUACUAGUGAUGUAUUCUCUCCCCAGAUGAAAUUGCUGCCUUAUUCAGAUUUACUCUCUUGAGCCAGAUUUUGAAUUUCACUGCAGACUGCUUCAGACUUCUAAUCAUAGGCUUGUAAACCUACUAAUAGGCUCUGCCCCUCUUCCCAAUACUUUUUGUCAUUUAGAGAUAUAAACCGGGGCAUAUAAAAAUGCAACUUGUAUUCCUUUGUAUAUUUUUCCCUGUCUGACUUAUAAAUCUUGAGACCUUUAUUGUAAAAGCAUGUAUCAUCAGGUGAGAAAUAUAAAUAGGAACUGGGGUCAUUGAGCCUCAGGUAGGGAAUAUAUCAACCCGAUUUCUUCCUCUCUUUUCCCUUUUAUAGGAUAAAUAAUCC